AAUCGGCACAUUGUGAGCAGGGGCUGCAGGAUGGAACCAGCAAGCUGCUGUGCUGAGCGCCCCAAACCUGGGCCUACAGGGGUGAGUGCCUCCCGUUACUCCUGCAGCAAGGACCCAGGGGGUGCCCCAGGCCACCCAGCCCCUCCCUUCCCCAGCCCACUUGCUCCCUGAUGUCUAACCCUCAUGACCCUUCUGACCCUGAUGCACGCCCAGGUGAAGACCAAGCCCUCCUGCGGGGGCUGGAGAGCCGUGAGCCUGCUCCUGCUGCUGCUGCUGCUGGUGCUGGCCGCUGUGGGGGUUGUGGCUGGAGGGCUUCUUGGCUCUGCUCAGGGCCCUCCCAAGCCAAGGCUGCAGACGCUGCGAAUGACCCUCCCGAGCCCCCACAUGCCCCGGCCCAACCAAACCAUCCUGGUGGACGUGGCCCGGAACGCGGCGACCAUCACAGUGACCCCACCUCAGAGCAACCACAGCUGGGCGGUGCUGUUCGACGGGCAGAGCGUGAGUGGGCAGGGAGGGGUCACCCUGGCAGGUGUCGGUCUGGGGGGCCCCGCCUCACCCCCCUGCCUCCCCAGGGCUGCAUCUGUUACCGCCCUGAGGAGCACCAGGUCUGCUUCCUCCGCCUGAUGGAGGACAGUGAUCGGGAGACCCUGCGGCUGCUGGUGGAUACCUCCAAGGUCCAAGAGGCUUGGGUCCCCAGCCAGGACACCCACCACACCCAGGAGCUGCUGGCAGUGCAGGGGAGCCUCGAAGUGGACCCCGCCCAGGCGGGGGCUUUGGUGCAGCGCCUGUGCAUGAGGACCCCCAUCUACUGGGCCCGGCGAGCAGAGGGGCCCCGGAGACAGCGGCUGAUUUAUCUCUGCAUCGACAUCUGCUUCCCGAGCAACAUCUGCGUGUCGGUCUGCUUUUAUUACCUCCCAGACUGAGCCCCCGACCUGGCCCAGCCUGGCCCGUCCCCAAUCCAGUGGGCUGGCCAGGCCACCUGCACCAGGGAGGACAGCUGCUGGCAGGGACUAAUAAACCCUUCCACCUGGC